GCGCAGAAAGCUGGCGGGGGGGUGGGGGGAGGAACAUGGCGCAAGCUCUGUCUGAGGAGGAGUUUCAGCGGAUGCAGGCUCAGCUCCUGGAACUCCGGACAAACAACUACCAGCUUUCAGAUGAACUACGCAAGAAUGGUGUUGAACUCACCAGUCUUCGACAGAAGGUCGCCUACUUGGAUAAGGAGUUCAGCAAAGCUCAGAAGGCACUGAGCAAGAGCAAGAAAGCUCAGGAAGUCGAGGUAUUGCUGAGUGAAAAUGAGAUGCUGCAGGCAAAGCUGCACAGCCAGGAGGAGGACUUCCGUUUGCAGAACAGCACACUAAUGGCCGAGUUCAGCAAGCUCUGCAGCCAGAUGGAACAGCUGGAGCAAGAGAACCAGCAACUGAAGGAGGGGGCUGCAGGAGCAGGGGUUGCCCAAGCUGGGCCCCUCGUGGAUGGGGAGCUGCUGAGGCUACAGGCUGAAAACACAGCCUUGCAGAAGAACGUGGCAGCCCUGCAGGAACGCUAUGGGAAAGAAGCCGGGAAGUUCUCAGCUGUCAGUGAGGGCCAGGGGGAUCCCCCAGGGGGCCUGGCCCCCACCGUCCUGGCCCCCAUGCCGUUGGCAGAGGUGGAGCUGAAAUGGGAAAUGGAGAAAGAGGAGAAGAGAUUGCUCUGGGAACAGCUGCAAGGCUUAGAGAGCUCAAAGCAGGCCGAAACAUCCAGGCUGCAGGAGGAACUUGCUAAGCUCUCCGAGAAACUGAAAAAGAAACAAGAAAGUUUUUGCCGUCUGCAGACAGAAAAGGAGACUCUGUUUAAUGACAGCAGGAACAAGAUUGAGGAAUUACAACAACGGAAGGAAGCUGAUCACAAAGCCCAGUUGGCUCGAACCCAGAAGCUGCAGCAGGAACUUGAGGCUGCCAAUCAGAGCUUGGCAGAGCUGAGAGAUCAGCGGCAGGGGGAGCGCCUGGAACAUGCAGCAGCUUUGCGGGCCCUACAAGAUCAGGUAUCCAUCCAGAGUGCAGAUGCACAGGAACAAGUGGAAGGGCUUUUGGCUGAGAACAAUGCCUUGAGGACUAGCCUGGCUGCCCUGGAGCAGAUCCAAACAGCAAAGACCCAAGAACUGAAUAUGCUCCGGGAACAGACCACUGGGCUGGCAGCUGAGUUGCAGCAGCAGCAGGCUGAGUACGAGGACCUUAUGGGACAGAAAGAUGACCUCAACUCCCAGCUCCAGGAGUCAUUACGGGCCAAUAGUCGACUGCUGGAACAACUUCAAGAAAUAGGGCAGGAGAAGGAGCAGUUGACCCAGGAAUUACAGGAGGCUCGGAAGAGUGCGGAGAAGCGGAAGGCCAUGCUGGAUGAGCUAGCAAUGGAAACGCUGCAAGAGAAGUCCCAGCACAAGGAAGAGCUGGGAGCAGUUCGUCUACGGCAUGAGAAGGAGGUGCUGGGGGUGCGUGCCCGCUAUGAGCGUGAGCUCCGAGAGCUGCAUGAAGACAAGAAGCGUCAGGAGGAGGAGCUCCGUGGGCAGAUCCGGGAGGAGAAGGCCCGGACACGGGAGCUGGAGACUCUCCAGCAGACAGUGGAAGAACUUCAAGCUCAGGUACAUUCCAUGGAUGGAGCCAAGGGCUGGUUUGAACGGCGCUUGAAGGAAGCCGAGGAAUCCCUGCAGCAGCAGCAGCAGGAACAAGAGGAAGCCCUCAAGCAGUGUCGGGAGCAGCACGCUGCCGAGCUGAAGGGCAAGGAGGAGGAGCUACAGGAUGUACGGGAUCAGCUCGAGCAGGCCCAGGAGGAGCGGGACUGCCACCUGAAGACCAUUAGCAGCCUGAAGCAGGAGGUGAAGGACACAGUGGAUGGGCAGAGGAUCCUGGAGAAGAAGGGCAGUGCUGCGCUCAAGGACCUCAAGCGGCAGCUGCAUUUGGAGCGGAAACGGGCAGAUAAGCUGCAGGAGCGACUGCAGGACAUCCUCACUAACAGCAAGAGCCGCUCAGGCCUUGAGGAGCUGGUUCUCUCAGAGAUGAACUCACCAAGCCGGACCCAGACAGGGGACAGCAGUAGCAUCUCCUCCUUCAGCUACCGGGAGAUCUUGCGGGAAAAGGAGAGCUCGGCUGUUCCAGCCAGGUCCUUAUCCAGCAGCCCUCAAGCCCAGCCCCCUCGGCCAGCAGAGCUGUCAGAUGAGGAAGUGGCUGAGCUCUUUCAGCGGCUGGCAGAGACACAGCAGGAGAAAUGGAUGCUGGAGGAGAAGGUGAAGCACCUGGAAGUGAGCAGUGCUUCCAUGGCAGAGGACCUCUGCCGGAAGAGCGCCAUCAUUGAGACCUACGUCAUGGACAGCCGGAUCGAUGUGUCUGUGGCAGCAGGCCACACAGACCGCAGCGGGCUGGGCAGCGUCCUGAGAGACCUAGUGAAGCCAGGUGACGAGAACCUUCGGGAGAUGAACAAGAAGCUGCAGAACAUGCUGGAGGAGCAGCUCACCAAGAAUAUGCACUUGCACAAGGAUAUGGAAGUUCUGUCCCAGGAAAUUGUGCGGCUCAGCAAGGAGUGCGUGGGGCCUCCUGACCCAGACCUAGAGCCAGGAGAAACCAGCUAAAGACCUGCAGGCUGCACCCACCUCCUCCCCUUCCUACCCCCUAGGAUGCUAUUCCCUUGGGCUGUGGUGGAAAAAUGAGGGCUGGAGCCAAAAUCAAAUAGCUUGGGAGACUGGACAUUAAAGGGGCUAGAGGCCUGAUGGUUAGUGUUAAUGAUCCUGUCUUAGGGCAGAGGCCACCAGGGAGUGGGGAUCCUGAGGGAAGGGGCAGGGAUUUCUCCUUCUUCUUGGUCCUGGCUCCCAAGGGCUUCUGUCUUCAUCUCUGCAUGAGCUCUCCUUCCCAGAGACCAACUCUUUUUAUUUUAUUUUAUUUUAUUUUUUAAUUUAUGUCUGGAGCCUGGCUACUCUGCAUUUGGGAUUGGGGAUGCUGGGUGGGUGUGUGGUCCAUGUUCAGCGUUCUAGCAACACGUGUGUGUGUGUGUGUGUAAAGGCUAUGCAGCCAAAAUACCAUCUGGCCAGACGGGCCCACCCAC